AACAAAAGUGCUGCAGCCGCUUGCUCCGGCCGGCACCCUAGGCCGGCCCGCCGCCAGCUGUCGCCGACAUGGAACCCUUGGCCAGCAACAUCCAGGUCCUGCUGCAGGCGGCCGAGUUCCUGGAGCGCCGUGAGAGAGAGGCCGAGCAUGGUUAUGCGUCCCUGUGCCCGCAUCGCAGUCCAGGCCCCAUCCACAGGAGGAAGAAGCGACCCCCCCAGGCUCCUGGCGCGCAGGACAGCGGGCGGUCAGUGCACAAUGAACUGGAGAAGCGCAGGAGGGCCCAGUUGAAGCGGUGCCUGGAGCGGCUGAAGCAGCAGAUGCCCCUGGGGGCCGACUGUGCCCGGUACACCACGCUGAGCCUGCUGCGCCGUGCCAGGAUGCACAUCCAGAAGCUGGAGGAUCAGGAGCAGCGGGCCCGACAGCUCAAGGAGAGGCUGCGCAGCAAGCAGCAGAGCCUGCAGCGGCAGCUGGAGCAGCUCCGGGGGCUGGCAGGGGCGGCCGAGCGGGAGCGGCUGCGGGCGGACAGUCUGGACUCCUCAGGCCUCUCCUCUGAGCGCUCAGACUCAGACCAAGUCUUGCCUAAUGAAAACGGGGGAACUCCCAACCACAGACCCACUGGAAGAGGAAAUAAUAUCAGUUCCCAUCACUGACACUGUUGGCCGUGCCAGGCAGUGCACUUAAUUCUCACAACUUGAGGCUGUUCUGUCUCCACUUCACGGAUGGUAGAAAUGAGGCUGAGUGACGUGACUCGCCUGAGGUCCAAAAACAGUGAAGCCAAGAUUCAAACCAGAGCCUUCCGACUCCAGAGCUGGGGCCAACUGAAUUCAACAAGUAUUUAUUGAGUGUCUAUUAUGUGCUAGAUACUGAGACACAUCAGAGAACAAAACCAAAAGCCCUGCCCUUGUCGGGCUUACAGUCUAGCACUUACCGCCAGUUAACCUGCAGGCUACCUGGAGCCCCGGGCAAGUCACCGCACCUCUGUGCCUCGGUCCUCAGCUGCCCAAUGGGAGAAUAAGCAGACCUGGCUCAGACAUGAAUCAUGUGCUUGGUGUACUGCAGAUGCCAAACUGCAUCCCCACAACCCACCACGUAGACAGCAGACAGGGCUGGAAGUUGAUUUUUAAUGAUAAAGUACAAUGAAGGGAGGGCAGAGAGGCUAAGCCUAGCUGUCUGGGGUGCUGUGGUGGUGGUAGACUGGCUACACAAACUGUUGCUGCUGCUGCUGCUUCUUGGUGGCCGCCUUGCUGGCGAGGUCCUUGGCCUUCUCUGUAGCUGCCAGUGCCGUCUCCUUUGCCUUCUCCUUGGCUUCCUUGGCUGUCUCAACAAGUGUUUUGGAAGGGGCCUCGCCUGUCGCGAACGGCAGGUGGCUGCCUUUAGAAGAUGCCUGAAAGACCAACCUAAUUUCCCUCCCCCAUGACACCAAUCUCCUCUGGGCCAGGCUCCACUAAAAAGGUGGUAUUCACCCUCCUCCCACCCCCAGUACAGACAAGGAGUCCCAGCUCAGAGCAGGGCAAUGACUAACCCAGACUCCACGCCCGCUAGGCUGAAUGAGCCUCUCCCUAUGAGGAAUAUCCACAUACCCAGAAACUCACCUUGCAGCUUAGCCAAGAUAUAUUCAAAACCCUUCAUAGUCUUGGUCACGUUGCUUUUGAAUCGGGCAAGACCAAAUUCCUGGCAUGAGAUGAGAAUGGGAAGGAUACUGAGUUGCCCACUGACCCCAGCCCAGCCCCAACACCGAAAGCACUGGGUCCCAGAGCCCCAGCAGCCCCAACAACACUGCUCACCUGGACAGCUCUGGAGACACCAAAUAAGCUAGAGGAGACCCAGGCUUCCCGGCGGAUUUCAGUCCAGCCACUGUUGUCAGAGUUCACACAGUAAACACAUCGUUCCUCCACCACCUAUGCAGAGGCCAACCACAAUCGUGGAACAGUCUUUCAUUUUGCCAACUUGCACAUAAAUCUGACUCCCUGUCACUUUUCAUGAGGCGAAGCAAUACAAUGAAAAUCCAUUCCUUCCCCUGACUGCACCUCCAAGUGGCACUGACAGAACAAGAAGCCAUAAAUAAGGUCGUUUUGCUCUCGAAAACCUCUCUUCUGACUCUUAAACUAGAAGGCAAAAGGUCUCUCUCUUGAGAUCAACAAAGGGCCUUCCAGCCCAUCCUGCUCCUGGAUUUUGUUUUGUGCAUCUAGACGCAUGCAGUGUUUUAGCCGCCUUCCACCAGCUGCAGCUCUGGAGCUUCCUGACAGUCCAAAUAAAAACAUUUGCCCGGC